CUGAUCUUGAAAGUAAUACUUGCUUGUCUUUAAAAAACGCAAACAAUGUAGAAGUGUAUAAUGUUGAAAAUAAAAGCCUUCUUGCCAUCAUUCCUAAUUCUAUAAAUAACUACUGCUAAUAGUUUGAUGAAUCUCAUGUAUGACAAGGACUUGGUACUUCUGUCACCAUUUUUUAUUUUCUCCCUUAUGACACCAAUAAUUCAUCAUAGUAUUCUUUUCCCUUGAGCUUGGAUAUUCUCAAUUGGCCAUUCUUGGCAGCUAUUUUUGAUAGACUAGAGUUGAUGUUUAUGAUGAAACCAGUUGACCAUCCUUGGUAUAUAUAAUUUUAAUCCUUUACACAUAAAUAUGCACAUUAUUUAGGUGAUUUUUAGAGACUGUUGCUGUUGGAAUAUUAGUGGAAAGUUGUGGCAUUUUUGAGCUGAAAAGCCUUUAAAGAUUAUCUGAUAGCCCUACUAUUUGAUAUGAGAUGAGGAAACGUUCUUUUAUAAAAAAUUACUCAGUUUUUAUUUAUAUAGAGAUGAGAAAGAUAAACAUGGAAGUAAAAAGAAAAUAAAUUUUGAAAUACCCAACUUAUUAAAAUAUGAUAGAAUUUUGUUGAAGAAUAUAAAAUCAAGACCUGAAGAAAUGGAGGUGCGUGAUACGUUCCUAGAAACAUAAAGUUAAUGUCAUUAUUAACAUGUCAGACCAGGUGCAGUGGCUCAUGUGCGUAAUCCCAGCACUAUGGGAGGCCAAGGCAAGUGAUUGCUUGAGUCCAGCAGUUGGAGACCAGCCUGAGCAACAUGGCAAAACCCCAUCUCUACAAAAAAUACAAAAAUUAGCCAGGCCUGGCUGCGCACCUGUAGUCCUAGCUACUUAGGAAACUGAGAUGAGAGGAUCACCUGAGCCUGGGGAGGUAGAGGAUGUAGUGAGCCAUGAUUGUGCCACCGCACUCCAGCCUGGGUGACAGAGUGAGACUCUGUCUGCAAAAAAAACAAAAACAAAAAAAGUCAAUCCUUUGUAAAUUAAUACAUACAUUUGAUACAAUUACAAUGAGAGUCUCAACAGGUAAGUUUACAAGUUGAUUCUAAACUUCAUCUUGAAGAAUAAAUGUGCCAGAAAACCCAAGGAGAUUUUGAAAAAGCAAAGUUGUAAAUAAGAUUUUUGUCUACCACAUGUUGAAGUAUACUGUAAAGUUGUUGAUUUAAAAAUAAGCGUGAUACUGGUAUAGAAGAUGAGAGGAGCAGAAUGUAGAAACCAGGAACAGAUCGAAAUGUACAUGAGAACUUAUUAUAAAAGUGGCAGUUUAAUUAAGUGUGGGAUAUUUUAAGAGAUAGGAAAAACCAAAGUUGUUUUUGCUAUUCUCAAACUCAACACAGCACAGAACACUUCUACACCAGAUGUGUGGGGUUUUUUCCCCACACCCUGCAAUUCAGUUCAAUUCUGACACUAACCAAAAAUUAGUGCAGGACCCAUAGUUUAGGGGCUCAGUCACACAGGACUGCCCUCCACUUUAUAUGCCAUUUGUAAGUCUUAGGUUGUGCCCUGUACUUCUGACCAACCAGCUGUAAAUUGAGGUUCUCAGGACCCCUUUCUUGGUCCAGUUAUUUGCUAGGAUGGGAAACACUUAGGUUUACCCAUGUAUUAUAAAGGAUACUACAGAAGAUGCAGAUGAUUAGCAAAAUACAGGGCGAGGUCUGGAAGGGUCCGGAGUGCAGGAGCUUCUUUCCCCACUUUCCCAGCAUAUGGAUGUGUUUCGUAAUCUGGGAACUCUCUGAAACCCAUGGUUCAGGGAAUUUUAUGGAGGCUUCAUCACAUGGGUAUAAGAAACUCAAUCUCUAGCCCUGCUUCCCUUCCCAGAGGAUGGGGAGUAGGUUGGUGGGGCUGAAGGUUCUAAGUUUCUGUUCAUGGCUUUAUCUUUCUGGUGACCAGCCCACAUCCAGGAGCCCAACAAGAGUUGCCUCAUUAGAAAAAGACACACUUGUCACCUAGGAAAUUCCAAGGGAUUAGGAGUUCUGUGUCAGGAAUUGAGGACAGAGACUAAAUAAUUUUUUUUUUUUUUUUUUUUUUUUGGGACGGAGUGUCACUGUCGCCCAGGCUGGGGUGCAGUGGUGCAAUCUCGGCUCACUGCAACCUCUGUCUCCCGAGCUCAAGUGAUUCUUCCACCUCAGCCUUCCAAGUAGCUGGUAUUACAAGCACCCACCACCACACCUGGCUAAUUUUUGUAUUUUUAGUAGAGACAGGGUUUCGCCAUGUUGGCCAGGCUGGUCUUGAACUCCUGACCUCAAGUGAUCCGCCCGCCUUGGCCUCCCACAGUGCUGGGAUUACAGGUGUGAGCCACCAUACCCGGCCUACAUAUUUCUUAAUACAGGCUGAGUAUCCCUUAUCUGCAACACUUGGGACCAGAAGUGUUUUGGAUUUUGGAUUUGUUUUGAGUUUAGAAUAUUUGCAUUAUACUUAUCGGUUCAACAUCCCCAAUCUGAAAAUCUGAAAUAUGAAACACCCCAAUGACCAUUACCAUUGAAUGUCAUGUUGGCACACAAGAAGUUUUGGAUUUUGGAGCAUUUUGGAUUUUGGAGUAUACAGGGAUACUCAACCUGUAUAUCACAGUAUCAUAAUGUAAAUUAUUCAAAUUGAGCUGUGAUAAUUAUCUUAUUAUAUAACUUUAAAAAAGUUAAUUUUUUAAAGAUAAAUUUAGAGCUUUACCUAACACCCUACACAUAAAUAAAAUUUAAGUAUAUAAACGUCAAGCACUUUUUCCACGAAGGUUCACAUGGCCUUGAGAGUACCAAAUGUAAAACAGCUCAUCAUUAGUUGUUGAAAUUAUUGCCAUUAAACAAGUAUACUAACUGGCCAUGUAUUCCUUGAGUAGAAUGGUGGGUAGAAUAAUCUCUGGCAUGUAUUUAUGUAGUCAUUUUCCAAAUAUUUAUUGAGUACCUAUACAUUGGGGAUACUCUUCCCUCAUGGAAUUUAUAGUUAGGGGCAUAAGGAGGGACAGUUAGAUAAGUAAAAUGUAUAUAUGUUAGGUGGUGAUAAGUGCUACAUAGAAAAAUAAAGCAGAAAAGGAGGAUAGGAGUGACAGAGUGGAGUUUUACAGUUUUAAAUAACCUGAUCAGGAAAGAUCUCACUGAGAAGAUAGGAUUUAAGCAAAGACCUGAAGGAGGAAAGGUAAUGAGCAUGGAGAUAAUUGGGGAAAUAAUAUUUCAGGUAUAGAGAUUUGCAAAUGCUAAGGCUCUAAAGUGGUACCCACAGUGACUGGAUCACUUUGAAGGAGGAGAAUAGUAAAAGAUAAGCUGCGAAAAUAUCAGGAAGUCAAGCCUGUAUUCAUUGUAAGGAGUUGGCAUUUAUUCUGCAUAAGCUGUGAAGCUGCCUGGUUUUUAGCAGAGGAAUGAUGUGAUGUAACUUAAAAAGUUUAACCAGAUUGGGUUGCUGUAUGGAAAGUAAACUUUAAGAGAGCAAAGGCAAAAGCAAGAAUAUCAGUUAAGUGACUAAUAGAACAACGCUAUGAGAGAUGAUAGCUUAUGAUUUGCUUAUGAAUUAUAUACAGAGUAUGGGAGAAGGAGCAAGAUAUCAGGGAGGACUCCAAGAUGUCUGGCAUGAUUAAGGGUAGAGUUUCCAUUAACUGAGGUAGACAGACCUACUGCAGAAGGUUUUGGGAGCAGAUCAUACAUCAUUGAACUAAGAUGCCACCACUUGUAGCUUCCAAUUAAAAUUAAACUAGCACAGAUAGUUUGAAAUGUGCAUCCCAGUUUCAGAGAUGUUAAAAUGUUUUUUUAAAAAAGGAACUUUUCGGAAUCAAACAUGGUAAAGUUUGAGAUGCCUAGUAGAUACUCAGGCAGAGCUGGGCACGGUGGCUCAUACCUGUAAUCCCAGCACUUAGGGAGGCAGAGGCGGGAGGAUUGCUUGAACUCAGGAAUUCACCAACCUGGGCAACAUAGCGAGACUCCAUCUCCACACACACACAAAAAGGUCUGAGAUUCAGGUAGAAAUGUUUUUAGUGGGCAGUUAGAUAUAUAAACCUGUCAUUCUUGGAGAAGUCUGAGCUGAAGAUAAACACAUUUGGGAAAUCAUUAGUAUUAUGAUGGAUUAAAUCACCAAUGAAGCAGGGAUAGAUAAAGAAGAGUUCUAAGAACGUAUCUGCUACAGUGCACCGUUUAGAGAUUGAACAUAGGGAAAACUAGGAAAGGAAACUGAGAGUUGGCUAGUGAGUCAGAAGAAUACAGUACUUGGAAACCAGCACUUGGAACAACUUCAGGAGGAGUCAGUUGUCUAUCACCUGUGUCUGAUACUGCUGAUAGGUCAAGUAAAUUGAGAACAGAGUUUAUUAUCCGCAUUUAUUGAGUUGGUCAUAUCAUUUAAGUUGAAGAAUUAAUUAAUUCCCUGAUGUUUGCUCAAUUUUGCAUUCUUAGAAUAACCCAGUUUGGUCAUAGUAUUUUUGAUGUGUUGCUAGAUGGGUUUUCUAGUAUUUUAUUUAGAAUUUUUACAUCCGUAUUUUGUUUGUGAAAGAUAUUUGUAGUUUGAAUGUUUGGUUAAGCUUACUGUUUAAAAAAAUCUGAUGUGUGUUAUAGGGUGUCUUGCAAAAAAAAUCAUCUGGCUUUUUUUUUUUCUAACUAUACUGAUUUAAUUUUUUUCUAACUACUGAUUUCAUUUAUUUAUAGUAAUCGGUUGCUUAGAUUUUUCUGUUUAUUCUUGGAUUACUGUGGUUAUUUAUACUUCGUAAAGGAUUUUCCCAUUUUUCUUAGUUUUAAAUUUUAUUGACAUGAAUACCAUCCUCUUAUUUGAGUUUACUAUAUAUAUUAUUUUAUACAAAACAGUAUGUCUUCUAAAGAUUGACUUGUCAAUUUUAGUAGUUUUUUUCAAUGAACUAACUUUUGCAUUUGUCGUAUAUCAUGGUUUUCUAUUUCAUUAAUUUCUAUUCUUACCUUUACUGAUUCUCAUUUUUUGAAAUGGAUAUUUAUUGCACUAAUUUUUAGUCUUGUUUACCCUAAUAUGAACAGUUAACGUUAAAAAUGUCCCACUUACUACUUUAGCUCCAUCUCUCAAAUUUUAGUAUAUAGUAUUUACUGUUUUUCAGUUCUGAAUAUUUUCUUUAUGAGUUCAUAAUUAGAAGUUGUUUCUAAUGUAGUGAUUUUCUUAUUUUUUAGUAUUGGUUUCUACUUUGAUUGUAGUGCAGUUAAAUAUAUAGAGAUACUGGUUUUAUGUUACUCAUCCUUUGAAAUGUCUUUCUUUUUGUAGUGAACUUUAGUAAUUGUUCUUUGGCUAAAAGAAUAAGUUUUCUUUUGUAGAUACCUGCAGUGUUCUGUAUUUGUGCAUUAGUGCAAGUUUAUUAGUUAUAUUGUCAAAUCUUCUAUAUUUUUGCUGAUUUCAGUUGUCAGAUUGAUACCUUAAUUACUGACAAAGGUGUAUUACACUAUUCCUCUAUGCAGAUUUGUGAAUUUUCCUUGUCCUGUCAAUUUUCGCCUUAUGUAUUUCUAGGACAUUAUUAGUUGCAUCUAAGAUUAAAAUUGUUUAUCUUCUCGCUUAGUCGCCCAGGCUGGAGUGCAGUGGCGUGAUCUCGGCUCACUGCAGGCUCCGCCUCCCGGGUUCACGCCAUUUUCCUGCCUCAGCCUCCCGAGUAGCUGGGAUUACAGGCGCCCGACACUACGCCCAGCUAAUUUUUUGUGUUUUUAGUAGAGAUGGGGUUUCACCGUGUUAGCCAGGACGGUCUCGAUCUCCUGACCUCGUGAUCCACCCACCUCGGCCUCCCAAAGUGCUGGGAUUACAGGCGUGAGCCACUGCGCCCGGCCGUGAAUUCAACUUUCUGUUGUUAGUGAAGAAGAUGGAUGAAUAGAUGGGAGGUGUGGAGCAGUAGUACUUCUAAAAGCGAGAAAUAAGUUCAGGGCUUCUGGAAAUCUUGUAAUCACCCGUGAGAUUGAUGUGGCAAAAAAUCAGUCCUUUUGGUUCAUCAACAAAAAAUCUACAACCCAGAAAAUAGUGGAAGAGAAAGUUGCAGCCUUAAAUAUUCAAGUGGGGAAUCUUUGCCAGUUUCUCCCUCAGGACAAAGUUGGAGAAUUUGCUAAACUCAGCAAAAUUGAACUCCUCGAAGCCACUGAAAAGUCAAUUGGUCCCCCAGAAAUGCACAAAUAUCACUGUGAACUCAAAAACUUAAGGGAGAAAGAAAAACAGCUCGAGACCUCAUGCAAAGAGAAAACUGAGUAUCUACAGAAAAUGGUUCAGAGGAAUGAAAGAUAUAAACAAGAUGUGGAGAGGUUCUAUGAACGGAAGCGACAUUUAGAUUUAAUUGAGAUGCUUGAAGCAAAAAGGCCAUGGGUGGAAUAUGAAAAUGUUCGUCAGGAAUAUGAAGAAGUAAAACUAGUUCGUGACCGAGUGAAGGAAGAGGUCAGAAAACUUAAAGAAGGGCAGAUUCCUGUAACAUGUCGAAUUGAAGAAAUGGAAAACGAGCGUCACAAUUUGGAGGCUCGAAUCAAAGAAAAGGCAACAGAUAUUAAGGAGGCAUCUCAAAAAUGCAAACAGAAGCAAGAUGUUAUAGAAAGGAAAGAUAAACAUAUUGAGGAACUUCAGCAGGCUUUAAUAGUAAAGCAAAAUGAAGAGCUUGACCGACAGAGGAGAAUAGGUAAUACCCGCAAAAUGAUAGAGGAUUUGCAAAAUGAACUAAAGACCACGGAAAACUGCGAGAAUCUUCAGCCCCAGAUUGAUGCCAUUACAAAUGAUCUGAGACGGAUUCAGGAUGAAAAGGCAUUAUGUGAAGGCGAAAUAAUUGAUAAGCGAAGAGAGAGGGAAACUCUAGAGAAGGAGAAAAAGAGUGUGGACGAUCAUAUUGUACGUUUUGACAAUCUUAUGAAUCAGAAGGAAGAUAAGCUAAGACAGAGAUUCCGUGACACGUAUGAUGCUGUUUUAUGGCUAAGAAAUAACAGAGACAAAUUUAAACAAAGAGUCUGUGAGCCCAUAAUGCUCACGAUCAAUAUGAAAGAUAAUAAAAAUGCCAAAUAUAUUGAAAAUCAUAUUCCAUCAAAUGACUUAAGAGCCUUUGUAUUUGAAAGUCAAGAAGAUAUGGAGGUUUUCCUCAAAGAGGUUCGUGACAAUAAAAAAUUAAGAGUAAAUGCUGUUAUUGCUCCCAAGAGUUCAUAUGCAGACAAAGCACCUUCAAGAUCUUUGAAUGAACUUAAACAAUACGGAUUUUUCUCUUAUUUGAGAGAAUUAUUUGAUGCACCUGAUCCUGUAAUGAGUUACCUUUGCUGUCAGUAUCAUAUUCAUGAAGUUCCUGUAGGAACUGAAAAGACCAGAGAAAGAAUUGAACGGGUAAUACAAGAAACCCGAUUAAAACAGAUUUAUACAGCAGAAGAAAAGUAUGUGGUGAAAACUUCUUUUUAUUCAAACAAAGUUAUUUCUAGUAACACAUCUCUAAAAGUAGCGCAGUUUCUCACUGUCACUGUGGACCUAGAGCAGAGAAGACACUUAGAAGAACAGCUAAAGGAAAUUCAUAGAAAAUUGCAAGCAGUGGAUUCAGGGUUGAUUGCCUUACGUGAAACAAGCAAACAUCUGGAGCACAAAGACAAUGAACUUAGACAAAAGAAGAAGGAGCUUCUUGAGAGAAAAACCAAGAAAAGACAACUGGAACAAAAAAUCAGUUCCAAACUAGGAAGUUUAAAGCUGAUGGAACAGGAUACUUGCAAUCUUGAAGAGGAAGAGCGAAAAGCAAGUACCAAAAUCAAAGAAAUAAAUGUUCAAAAAGCGAAACUUGUUACCGAAUUAACAAACCUAAUAAAGAUUUGUACUUCUUUGCAUAUACAAAAAGUAGAUUUAAUUCUCCAAAAUACUACAGUGAUCUCUGAGAAGAACAAAUUAGAAUCAGAUUAUAUGGCCGCAUCUUCACAACUCCGUCUUACAGAGCAACAUUUCAUUGAAUUGGAUGAAAAUAGACAGAGAUUAUUGCAGAAAUGCAAGGAACUUAUGAAAAGAGCUAGGCAAGUAUGUAACCUGGGUGCAGAGCAGACUCUUCCUCAAGAAUACCAGACACAAGUACCCACCAUUCCAAAUGGACACAACUCCUCACUCCCCAUGGUUUUCCAAGACCUUCCAAACACAUUGGAUGAAAUUGAUGCUUUAUUAACUGAAGAAAGAUCAAGAGCUUCCUGCUUCACGGGACUGAAUCCUACAAUUGUUCAGGAAUAUACAAAAAGAGAAGAAGAAAUAGAACAGUUAACUGAGGAACUAAAGGGAAAGAAAGUUGAACUAGAUCAAUACAGGGAAAACAUUUCACAGGUAAAAGAAAGGUGGCUUAAUCCUUUAAAAGAGCUGGUAGAAAAAAUUAAUGAAAAAUUCAGCAAUUUUUUUAGUUCCAUGCAGUGUGCUGGUGAAGUUGAUCUCCAUACAGAAAAUGAGGAAGAUUAUGAUAAAUAUGGAAUUCGAAUUAGAGUCAAAUUUCGAAGUAGUACUCAACUGCAUGAAUUAACUCCUCAUCAUCAAAGUGGAGGUGAAAGAAGUGUUUCUACCAUGUUAUACUUGAUGGCACUUCAGGAGCUAAAUAGAUGUCCAUUCAGAGUAGUUGAUGAAAUCAAUCAGGGAAUGGACCCAAUCAAUGAACGGAGAGUGUUUGAAAUGGUUGUAAAUACUGCCUGUAAAGAAAAUACAUCUCAAUACUUUUUCAUAACACCAAAGCUCCUGCAAAAUCUUCCUUAUUCUGAAAAGAUGACAGUUUUGUUUGUCUACAAUGGCCCUCAUAUGCUGGAACCAAACACAUGGAAUUUAAAGGCUUUCCAAAGGCGGCGGCGCCGUAUUACAUUCACUCAACCUUCUUAAUAAAAGUAAAGAGAGGGAACUUGGGAAUUUUUUUUGUUAAAUUCUGUUUAUAAGUAUGGCUCAACUGAAUAAAAGGAGAUUCACUAAAACGAAAAGCAGUUAUUUUUGGAAACCUGCUUUUAAAUACAAAUAGGUUGAUAAUGGAAACUAUAAUGACCUUUCCAAAAUAGCAGCUGGUAGUAAAAGUUAAGUCUUCUUCAGUCUUGGUUGAACUUGAGUUCUUGGCACUCUGACCAUGAGUCAUUCAGUUCUCAUGUUAAAAUGUACUUAAUAUUACAAAUCAAAGGUACAGUGGAAGAAGGGUUAAUCACAAGAAGUUACUUAUAUGGUAGCCCUGAGCUUUAAUUGCAGAGUAACUUUAAUUACUUUUAGAGCCUAAAGAUGACUCUAGAGCCUAAGUCCUAGUUUCUCCCAAUGUUAUAUUUAAUUUUAAAAAAUUGAUAUGAAAAUGUCUAAUGUAUAGUAAUAAUUUAUGACAGAUCUAGUCAUUUCUUCCUAUUAAAAAAGAUUACCUUAUCUCCAGUAGGAAAUGGAAUUUUAUGGGCCUUUAAAAGAAAGUUUUAUGAAACUUGAUGCUAUAAUUUUAUUGGUAUUUCAAGGGGAAAAAAGCACUGGGGUUCAAAAAUGGUAGCAGAACUGCUUUGAAAUGCUGCAAGGUGGCCACUAGAUGAUGCAAAAUACAACCAAAAGAUUGACUGAGAAUAAAAUUAGGUGACAAGGGUUUUUAAAGAAUAACCUUUUAAAGUGUGGGGGCAGGGGUUGCUUUUUUUUAUUUUAUUUAAAGUCAAUUAUAUUUUACAUCUUACAUUUCUAAAAGCAUUUUAUAAUUAUUUUUAGUAAGAUUUUUCUUAAAAUUUCAUAUACUGGUUUCUACAAUUUAUAUUUGAAAUUUCUCAGUGUUAUGUAAAGAGUGAUGGAAAAGCAUUGAUUUCUUUAAAACCGUAAUGUUUUUAGAACUUAAGCCUAUAGGGCCUUUCUUACAAUGUUGAUGUACCCAUUAUCUUAGAAAAUCUAGUUUAAACUGUUUUCUUUCACCGCAAAAGAAUUAAAUGGGAAAAUCAUUUGUUUAUCUCUAAGUUAUACUAAUUAGUAGAACCAAACAAAUUAUCUUCUUUUAAAAAAUAAAUCUUAUAGGAAAAUAGACAGUCCAAAGUCAUGUCUUUGAACAGUGGAUUGGAUCUGUGCCAGUAAUGACAAAAUUAUUUUUUUGACUUGCUUGCCUGAAUAAAUUGAAGAAUUGCUUUCAGUUUGGGUUUUGUAUAUUCUUAAGUAGCCAUUGAAAUUUAUAUUCUUAACUAGGUCAAAAAAUAAUGAGCCAUAAGUUUAUGUCCUCUCACUUAGACAUUUUCUCUUUAAAAAGGUAUUUUCUUCUUUAUAAACAUUUUAAAAGAGCCUUCCCUUCUUAAACUAACUCCAGUGCAUGAAGUGUGAAAAUAUUUUAAAAUGACAUUUUUACUAAUAUGAGCAAGUCAUGUAAACAUUGAAGAACUUGGUAACAUAUUAGUAAAUGGAUAUUACCAAAUGUUUUCAUCGUUAAUUACUUUGCGUUCCACCAAAAUAUCUUUACUAAAAUGUGCUUGGUGUAGUUUGUUUAUUGUCUAAAUUAGUACCAGUCAUCUUAUUUCUGCAAAAUGAGUAUCAAUGUGAAAAAGACACGUGAAGAUUAAGCAUGUUUGAAAAUAAAAUGGUCAAUUACAUUUCAAUUUACAUAGGCCAACAACUGUUCCAUACUUUGUUUGUAAACAUUUAAUUUCUCUACUGGACAAAAUUAAUAUUUGGCUUUACAUUGAAUUUUGAGCUGUGAAGAAUAAAUUAUGUAUCAUUUUAGCAUAUUAAACAGUAGUAAGUCUAGCACAUAGUCUCAGCCACUUAAAACAAAAGUUUUUUUGUUUGUUUGUUUGUUUGUUUUUUUGAGAUGGAGUCUCACUCUGUUGCCCAGGCUGGAGUGCAGUGGCGUGAUCUCGGCUUACUGCAACCUCCGCCUCCCGGGUUCAAGCGAUUCUCCUGCCUCAGCCUCCCAAGUAACUGGGACAACAGGCGCGUCCCACCACACCCAGCUAAUUUUUUAUACUUUUAGUAGAGAUGGGGUUUCAGCAUAUUGGCCAGGCUGGUCUCGAACUCCUGACCUUGUGAUCCACCCGCCUCGGCCUCCCAAAGUGCUGGGAUUAUAGGCGUGAGCCCCUGCACCCGGCCAAAAGUUGAUUUUUAAUUACAUAAAAAUCGUAAAAACUUCUAGUAAAAACUUGAUUUGGUGAAUACAGUUAUAUUUAAAAACCUUAAGGUGACAAGCAUUUUCUAUGCCUAAAUCUUCAUUGGUUUGCCUGGAAAGAGUCUCUGUUAAAAGAUUUUCCAUAUUCAAAGUAAAAGGAAAGAUUUCUUGCUUUCUAAUUGUCUUUUGGACACAUGCCUAUUUUCUUUGAGGUAUAAACCUUUAGAUGUGAAAAAUGUAAUUUCAUUCUGCUAUUGUGUGUGCUUGUGUGUGUGUAAUUGAAAAAACUGGGAAAUCCUGCUUUGUUGGUAAUAAAUCAAUAUUUUUAUAUUC